ACUCCAGCUUGGGUGACAGAGCGAGACUCCGUCUCAAAAAAAAAAAAAAAAGGCAACAUCAACAGAGUAAAGGGGCAACUCAAAAGAUGGGAGAAAAUGUUUUUUUUUUUUUUGAGAUGGAGUCUCCCUCUGUCACCCAGGCUGGGGUGCAGUGGUGCAAUCUUGGCUCACUGCAACUUCUGCCUCUCGGGUUCCAGCAAUUCUCCUGUCUCAACCUCCCAAGUAGCUGGGAUUGCAGGCGCAUGCUGCCGUGCCCGGCUAAUUUUUUGUAUUUUAGUAGAGACGGGGUUUCACUGUGUUGCCCAGGCUGGUCUCAAACUCCUGAGCUCAGGUGAUCCACCCACCUCGGCCUCCCAAAGUGCUGGGAUUACAGGUGUGAGCCACUGCACCCAGCUGAUGGGAGAAAAUAUUUACAAAUCAUUUAUCUGAUAAGGCACUAAUAUCCAGAAUAUAUAGAGAACUCCUAAAACUCUAAGACAAAAAACUCAAUUUAAAAAUGGGCAGAGGACAUGAAUAGACAUCUCUCCAAAGAUGAUCUACAAAUGGUCAAUAAGCAAAUGAAGAGAUUCCCAACAUCAUUUAUUACUGAGGAAAUGCAAAUUAAAACUAUAAUAGGACAUCACCUCACACCCAUUAAGAUGACUACUAUCAAAAAAACCCCAAAAUAACAAGUAUUGGCAAGGAUGUGGAGAAUCUGGAACCCUGGAGAACUAUUGAUGGGAAUAUAAAAUGACACAGUUCCUAUGAAAAACACGAUAAGAGUUCCUCAAAAAAUUAGAAAUAGAAUGACUGUAUGAUCCCACAUUGCAACUGUGGGUAUAUACCCAAAAUAAUGGAAAUCAGGGUCUUGAAAAUAUAUUUGUAUACUCAAGUUCAUAGCAGCGUUAUUCACAACAGCUAAAAUGCAAAAUCAGUUCAAGUGCCUACCAAUGAACAAACAGAUAAGCAGAAUAUUAUUUAGCCUUAGAAAGAAAGGAAAUUUCACCUUACAAAGGAAGGACAUAUGCUAUAAUAUGGAUCACCCUUGAGGACAUUAUGCUAAGUAAAAUAAGCCAGUCACAAAACACAAAGAUUGUGUCAUUCCACUUAGAUGAGGUACUUAGAAUAGUCACAUUCAGAGAGACAGACAGCAGAUUGGUGGUUGCCAGAAGCUGGGGGGAGCAGAAAUGGGGAGUUGUUGUUUAAUGAGUGCACAGUUUCAGUUUCACAAGAUGAAGUGUUAUGGAGAUGGAUGGGGUGACGUUUAUACAUGAUGAAUGUUUUUAAUGCCACUCAACUGUACACUUUAAAAUGGCUAAGAUGGUAAAUUUUAUGUUAUAUGUAUCUUUUUUUUGAGGCAAAGUCUUGCUCUGUCAUUUCUUUUACUAUACCUUUUAAGGUGUCUUUUUAGCAGAUGCCCUAGGGAUUACAAUUAAUAUCUUAAUUUAUAACAACUGAUCUCAGAUUAAUUAUAAUUUAAUGUCAAUGGUAUACAAAAACUUUGCGCAUAUAUAGCUCUGUUCCCUCCUCCUCCUCUGUGCUAUCACUGUCAUAUAAUUUAAAUGUUUACACAUCAUUUGACUACCAGCACAGAUGUCUAAUCAUCACUCUCUGCAGUUGUCUUUUAAAUCAGGUAGGAGAAAAAAGAGCUACACACAUAAACUAUUUAUUUUUACACUGCCCUUUGAAAAUGUUUUCCCCAAUUUUUUAUUGUAAUAAAAUACACAUAACAGGCCAGGCACAGCAACACACGCCUAUAAUCCCAGCACUUUGGGAGGCCAAGGCUAGUGGAUCUCCUGAGGUCAGGAAUUUAAGACAAGCCUGGCCAACACGAUGAAACACCGUCUCUACUAAAAAAUACAAAAAAAAAAAAAUUAGCCAGGCGUGGUGGCGGGUGCCUGUAAUCCCAGCUACUCAGGAGGCUGAGGCAGGAAAAUUGCUUGAAACUGGGAGGAGGAGGUUGCAGUGAGCCAAGAUCACACCACUGCCUGGGCAACAGAGCAAGACUCCGUCUCAAAAAAAAAAAAAAAAAAAAAAAAGAAAUGACAAAUAUGUUGAAAUGAGACACUAGGAAAUAUCUAUUUAACACCAAAGAAGGCCAUAUGGAAACAGAGGAACAAAAAAAACCUAAGAUAUGGAAAACAAAUAGCAAAUGGUGUGCCUAAAUUCUCCCUUAUCAACUCAGUAUGUAGUGUCAACUAAAUGUUAAUUAAACACUCCAGUUAAAAAGCAGCGGAUAGAAGGGCUGACUUUUAAGAACCAUGAUUCAACGCACAUUCAAAGACACUCUGAAGUAAAAGAGCAAAGAUAGAAUAGUAAGCAGAAGAGAGCUGGAGUGACUGUGACAAUAUGAAAGAAAACAGACCUUCGGACAAAAGUUGUUAAAACAGACAAGGAUAUUUUAUAGUGAUAAAAGGGUACAUCCAUCAAGAAAAUAUCACCGUUAUCAACAUAUGUGCACCUGACACAGAGCCCCAAGAUACAUGAAGCCAAAGCGGAAAUGAUGAAGGGCAAAAUGGACAAUUCAACAAUAACAGCUGGAGACUUCCAGCUUUCAAUAGCCCAUUUCCAAUCAUGGAUAAAGCAACAGGACAGAAAAUCAAAAGUCAGUAGAAGACGUCAACAGGCUCUAACCCACCUAGACUUGGCAGACGUCUGUAGAAUACUCCACCAACAACUGCAAAGGUUGUUGUGCCCAUUAUUCUCAAGUGCACGUGGAAUGUCUGACAGAAUAAACCCGAUGUUGUCAUAAAAUAAAUCUCAACAAAUUUAAAAUGAUUGAAAUCAUGCAAAGUAUGUUCUCUUACCACAAUUGAAUGAAAUUACAAAUCAAUAACAGAAAGAAAUUUGGGUAAUUAAAAAAUAUGUUAAUAAAACACUGAACUCCUUAGUAUCCAAUAGGGCAAAGAAGCAUUCACAAGAGAAUUUAGAAGAUAGUUUGAGAUAAAUGGAAAUGAAAACACAAUAUACUAAAAUACAGAUGAAGCUAAACAGUGCUUACAGGGAAAUGUACAGCUGUGGAUACUUACACUAAAUAAAAAGAGAUCUCAAAUCAAUAACCCAACCUUCCACCUAAAGAAACGAGAAAAAAACAGCACAGUAAGUCAAAGCAAGCAGAAGGAAAUAAUAAAUAGUAGAGCAGAGAUAAAUUACAGUAGAAAAAUAAUUUAAAAGAUCAAUUAAAACAGACCGGGUAUGGUGGCUCACACCUGUAAUCCCAGCACUUCAGGAGGCUAAGGCAGGCAGAUCUCUUGAGCUCAGGAGUUCAAGACCAGCAGGGGCAAACGGUAAAACCCCAUCUCUACAAAAAUAAAAAAUAGCUGGGUGUGGUGGCACGCACCUGUGGUCCCAGCUACCUGGGAGGCUUGAGCCCAGGAGGUCGAGGCUGCAGUGAGCCAAGAUCAUGCCACCACUGCACUCCAGCCUGGGCAACAGAGUGAGACCCUGUCUCAAAAAAAAAAAAAAAAAAAAGAAAGAAAGAAAGAAAAGAAAACAAAAAACAAAAGUUGGUUUUUGGAAGGCCAGGUGCGGUGGCUCACACCUAUAAUCCCAGCACUUUGGGAGGCUGAGGCGGGCGGAUCACAAGGUCGGGAGAUCGAGACCAUCCUAGCUAAGAUGGUGAAACCCCGUUUCUACUAAAAAAUACAAAAAACUAGCCGGGCAUGGUGGCACCCACCUGUAGUCCCAGCUACCCACGAGGCUGAGGUAGGAGAAUGGCUUGAACCCAGGAGGCAGAGCUUGUAAGUGAGCUGAGAUCAUGCCACUGCACUCCAGCCUGGGUGACAGAGUGAGACUCCAUCUCAAAAAAAAAAAAAAAAAAGUUGGUUUUUGAAAAGAUCAAGAAAAUUGAAUAGCCAGACUAAGAAAAAAGAGAAGACUCAAAUUUACUAAAAUCAGGAAUGAAAUAGAAGACAUUACUAAUGACAUUACAGAAAUUAAAAGAUUUAUGAGGGACUCUUAUGAACAAUGUGCCAACCAAUUAAAUAAUCUAAAUGAAAUGAACAAAUUCCUGGAAAGACACAAACUACUGAAACUGACUCAUGAAGACAUACAAAAUCUGAAUAGACCUAACACAAAUGAAGAGAUUGAAGUAGGAAAAAAAAAAACAAACAAAAAAAAACAAACUUCCCACAAAGAAAAGCCCAGGAUGAGAUGGCUUCCCUGGUGAAUUUUACCAAAUGUUUGAAGCAUAAUUAAUACCAAUCCUUCAUAAAUUCUUCCAAAAUAGGGAACACUUCCUCACUCAUUCAGAGGCCAGUAUUACCCUGAUACCAAAACUAGACAAAAUCGUCACACAAAAAAUAAACUUUCCAGUAUCUCUUAUGAAUAUAGCUGCAAAAAAUGUUCAACAAAAUACCAGUAAACUUAAUCCAGCAACAUUUUCGAAAAGAUUAUGCACAAUGAAUGCAAAGUUGGUUCAAUAUGAAUGAUUAGGCAAGAAAAUAAAAUUAGAGGCAGCCAGGUUGGCAAGGAAGAAGUAAAACUAUUUCUAUUUGCAGAUGACAUGAUUUCAUGCAUACAAAAUCAUCAGAAAUCCAUGCAAAAACAUUGGAGCUGAGAAAUGAGUUCUGCAAGGCUGAAAAUACAGACCAAUAUUAUAAAAAUCAGUCACGUUUCUAAAACAAUGAACAAUAUGAAAAUGAAAUUAAGAAAACGAUUCCAUUUAUAAUCACAUCAAAAGAAUAAGCUUAGGAAUAAAUUCAAUCAAAGAAGUACACAACUUGAACACUAAAAACUACAAAACAUCAUUAGAAGAAAUUAAACAUUUAAAUAUGUGGAAAGACAUCUUGUGUUCCUCAAUUAGAAGAAUUAAUAUUGUUAAGACAGCAAUAGUCCCCAUAUUGGUCUACAGAUUCAAUCCAAUCCCCAUCAAAAUUCUAACUGCUUUUUUUUUCUUUUUUUUUUUUUGCAGAAAUGGAAAGUCUGAUCCUAAAAUUCAUACGGAAUUGCAAGAGGCCUCAGAUUGCCAAAACUACCCAAUAAAAGAACUAAAUUGGAAGACUUACACGUCCCAAUUUCAAAAAUUACUACAAAACUGUAGUAAUCAAGACAGUAUGGUACUGGCUUAAGGCUAGGUAUAGAGACAAUGGAACAGAAUUGAAAGUCCAAAAAUAAACCCCUACUUUUAUGGUGAACUGGUUUCAACAAGGGUGCCAAAGUCACUCACUUGAGGAGAGAUCAGCUCCUCAGCAAAUGGUGCUCAGACAACUGGACCUCCAUUUGCAAAAGAAGGUAUUUGGACUCCUACCUCACACCAUAUACAAAAAAAUUAACCAUGUAUAAAAUUGAUCAAAGACCUAAAAGUAAAAGUCGUGAGUUUUGGCCCACAGGAGUAGACGGACAGGGUUGAGGAGCCAGUCUCCCAGUGAAGGUGCUGGAGGCUCCUUGAUGCUCUUCCCUGACAGUUCAGCCUAGAGUGCACUCCUUGGGAUGAUGGCGCCCCUCCUCUCACACCUUGGCUCAGAACUCAGCACUGAAAUCCACUGGGAAGGCCAGGGGCAGGAGAGACCUCUGCCUAGUGGGAGUGCAAGGACAGAGGCCUCCUCGGGCUGUGUAGGCCCUGCCUGGAGGGGACACCAGAACCAUAGGGUGUGUGCGAGGCAGCGGUUGGAUCAGUGUGGAGAGAGGGUGGAGGAGGUGCCCACAAGUUACCAAGGUUUGCAGUGAGUUCCUGUCAUUCUACAUUCAGGUACAUAGCUCCCAGGACAGCCAGCCCCUCCCCAUAGGCCUACACACCCAGCCUUCAGGCCACACCCAGGCUGGUGGCCGCAGACCACUUGGGUCCCUGUUUCCAGGGCUCUGAUGGGAUAGAAGAGACUCAGCCCCAUGAGGAUGUGGGUGCCCCUCAUCUCUCCACAGCAAGGAGGGGCCAGAGGAAGCCCCAUGCUAGCGUCAGGGGACAAGGAUUCCAGCUCAGGCCUGUCCACGGCUGUGUGACCCGGCAUGGGUUAAGCUCUCUCAAGGCCUCAGUUUCUUCCUCUGCAGAGUGUGGGAUGGGGGUGACCUCACCAGAUGGCCCCACAUGCUUUAGCACAGAGAUAAUCCCUUUCCUCGUGACCCACAGCCAGCCAAGCAGCUCUACUGAGUGUGGGACUCUGUCCAAGCUCUGAGUCAGCCCUAGGGCUGGUCUUGGCAGCCCUGUGCUGGCUGGCCAGGGUUGGCUGUGGAGCCAAGGAAAGGGAUUUGGAAUUCAGGGAUUUAUGCUUUAAAUUUCACAUUUUCUUUUUCCCAAUAGAGUUUCCUACUCUCAAUCUCUUGACACGAUGGUAAAGCCCUUUGCUGUAGCUAAACUCAGUUGCCAUUUUCGGAUUGGCAUUAGGGUGAGAAGGCUGAGUGCUCACAGGGAAGCCUCUUCCCAGCAGCACCCCUGGGCUGGAAAGGGCAGCGGGAGCAGCACAGAGCAGCAGAGGGUGGCUCAGGCUAAGCCGGAGCUGCCCGGGGCAAACAAAGAGGGACCUGCCUCCUUGUUUCUUAGCCUCUUAACACAGAAGCUCGCAGCCUGGAUUCUAGGAAGGCUUGGGGGGUACGGCCAUCCUGCUGGAAGCCUUUGCUCCUUUAGCCCAGAGAGCACUUGCCCCAGCCCCACAUACACCCCAGGGAGAUGCCACCGGCCAAGGAGAGGCUUGCUGAGGCCACGGCCCAGCAUCAAGCCCUCACAUCAGGCUGUUCCAGCAGCCAGGGGCCCUCAGAAGCAAGGCCGAGUGGAAGGAGGUGCCAGGGAGGGGGCAGAGCUCAAUGUCCACUGCAGCAGCUGCUGGGGUCCCUUCUCUGCUGCCACCUCAUCUGGCACAGGGUGGGGCAUGGGAUGGAGACAUCUGAGUACCCACCAGGCCCACACACAUAUGUGGACAUGCAUGCAUGCCACACACACGUGCACACACUUGUAUACGUACACAUGCCCGACACAGCUGCACCAUGCCAGAUACACGCCUCACACAUGGGUGCACACACACAGCACAUGUGCUCACACACCAUGCACAUGCCUGCAUCUGAGGCUGACCCUGCCUUUGAUCUGGAGGAUGCUAAUGGACCCUGCAGAGAGAAAGUGGAUGUCACUGCAGAGACUCAGUGGGCACUGGAGGGUGCAACGUCCCCUGUCCCAGUCUCUGCCCAGGUCCAUCCUGUCCCCUGCCCCACACACCCUUCAUCACUGGGUGUCCCCGUCACCGGGUAUCUGUCCUGGGGGAGUCCAGCACGCCAGGCCUGGCCUCUCUCCAGAGCCCCCCCAGUCUCAGUGGGCCCCACCCUGGGGCUGGGGAGGAGGAAUAGGAGUGUGGGGGAGCUGGGUGGGGACUGAGUCCUUUCUCCAGGAGGGAAGGUUGUGUGUCCCUACAGCCCUGUGUCACCAGAACACCUCCCCAGCAACAGGGGUCACUCCCGUAGGACCUGCCGCUGACCAUGGGACAAGAACGUGGGGGGCAUGGGAAGGAUGUGGAGGGGGCAUGGGAAGGAUGUGGAGGGGGCAUGGGAAGGAUGUGGGGGGUGUGGGAAGGAUGUAGGGGGCGUGGGAAGGACGUGGGGGGUGUAGGAAGGACAUGGGCGGUGUGGGAAGGACGUGGGGGGUGGUGUGGGAAGGACGUGGGGGGUGGCGUGGGAAGGACGUGGGGGGGUGGCGUGGGAAGGACGUGGGGGGGUGGCGUGGGAAGGACGUGGGGGGGCAGCGUGGGAAGGACGUGGGGGACGGUGUGGGAAGGAUGUGGGGGGUGUGGGAAGGACGUGCGGGUGGCGUGGAAAGGACGUGGGGGAGCUGUGGGAAUAACACGGGGGUGGCGUGGGCCCUGCUCCCUGUCCCUCUUCUUUGGACGAGGCUGCCAGUAUGUGGAACCCAGGGGGGUGCCCUGUGGCCCAGCAGCUGUUCCCACCUUCCCUGCAGCCACAAGCUUUGAAGUGGCCUUGCCAGAGGCCCCACAGGACGUCUCCGGGGAGCUGCGGCCAGACUUUGGGCACAGCAGGCAGUGCCUAUGGGGAGAGAGACACCCUCCGGCCGGCCUCCCUCCACCCCCAGCCCCACGACGGCAAAUGGGCUCCUCCAAGGGUCUUCGGCGAGGUGUGCGGGCCUCUUCUGCCAAGGCCAUGUCAUUGGGAGGUGGCCCAGUCAGGGUGGCAGGAAAAAGGACCAACGGGGCUCACCCGCAGGUCCCGAUAGAGGGACCACUUCAGAGGCGGUUCAAGGAGCCGAGCCCCAGGGUGGGAGGCCUGGGACCAGCCCCCGGGGGACAGCGACGGCCCCAGGCCUGGAGGACCGGAUGGAGCGGCUGGCGUGCCCUGCAGGGGGAGUGGGAAGAAACGGGGAAGCCGGGCCGCGGUAGCGCAGGCCGCAGGCAGGGCUGUGUGGGACAGGGCGGCUUGCACAGCUUAGCUUCUUCCUGGCCCGGGUGGGCUCCGUCCUCUUCUCUGGGCCAGCUGCGCCGGAGGCCCCGGGAAGAGUCCCCCUGCUCUGGCCCGCGGGACCUGCUCCCCAGCCUGGAAAGUCUGAGCUGGCCCCGCUGCCGGGACACCCUCCCCAGCCUCGCUGGUGGCCUGGUUUCUGCCGGGCGCGGGGGGAAUGUGGGUCAGCGUUUCCAAGUCUGGCCCGGGGCCAGAGGCAGUGGAAGGAAAAACACUCAGCGGGGGCUGCCUGGCAGAGGCCUCACCUCACAGCCGGCGGUUCCAACCCCGCAGCCAGCAGAGGCCUCACCCCACAGCCGGCGGCUCCAACGCCACAGCCGGCGACUCCAACCCCGCAGCCGGCGGCUCCAACCCCGCAGCCGGCGGCUCCAACCUCGCAGCCGGCGACUCCAACCCCGCAGCCGGCGGCCUCACCUCACAGCCGGCGGUUCCAACCCCGCAGCCGGCGGCUCCAACCCCGCAGCCGGCGGCUCCAACCCCGCAGCCGGCGUCUCCAACCCCGCAGCCGGCGGCUCCAACCCCGCAGCCGGCGGCUCCAACCCCGCAGCCGGCGGCUCAGGGCUCAGGACCACAGGGAGGGCGCCCCAGGCAGCUCCUCCUCCUGGGCUCUGCCCCCACCGCCGUCCUCUGGAGAUGGCCCGAGGCUGGUGCCCAUGACUCAAUGUCCCACUCCCGCAUCUCCUGCGGUCCCAGGGCGGGUCCCGCUGGUGUGUGGCCGGCCUCGCAGGAACCACUUCGCUCUCCCCCAUCCACUACUCCCACAGGCAACAGGACCGGCCCCCUGGCCCGUCGGUGGGCGCAUCAGCUUGGUGGCCCUGGCCCCCUGCGCCUCAGGGGUCCCUCACAGGCCGGCCAGCUUCCAGCACCCUCCCUAAGUCCUCGGCCCCUUGGAGGCUGCCAUGGCACCUGAACCUCCCCCCGCCUCUCCAGGCACAGCUCGAGGUUGGGCGGAUGGGGGCUGCAUCCCGGGCACCACAUGUGGGUAGGCACUGCCGCAGCCCCUCGAGUAGCCCUCAGCAAGCAGGGCUGGAGGGUGGGCUCUGUGCAAAACCGCCAUCACAGCCCCAGGGCCAUCAGCAGGCAGAGGCGCAAAGCCUGGUCAUGGCCAGCAGCCCUGGGAUGCCCCUGCCCCAGACCCCCCACCCCGGAGACCCCCAGCCCCAGGAUGCCCACACCUCAGCCUCCCAAGUAGUUGGGACUACAGGUGUGCACUACCACACCCAGCUGAUUUUUUUUUAUUUUUGUAGAGCGGUCUCGCUGUGUUGCACAGGCUGGUUUCGAACUCCUGGCUUCGAGCCAUCCUCCUGCUCAGCCUCCCAUGGUGCUGGGAUUGCAGGCGUGAGCCCCACGCCUGGCCACGCGCCUUGUUGAGUUGGUGACUUCGCCUUUGCUGUGGGGAUCUGGGUUGGGGUCUUGUGGCUUACAUGAGAAUAGAAGAUCAUGGGGUAGUUCCUGGCACCCUCCCCUCAAGGAGGCUCACACAGGCCAGGACCGCCCCCUCUGGCUGCCCCAUCGCUGCCCCCCGACAGGCCCUCUGCCUCUCCCCUGUGAACCACGAAGCACAUCGAUGGGGUGCCUAGCGCCCCGCCUCAGUCAGGGCUCAUGGGGGAGGCCCUUCUUUAACGUCUCUUACUGGGCACACCCAGAGGCCACGUGUUCCAGGGUCAGAGAGACCAGGAGAAAUCCCAGCUUCUUCACUCACGGCUGUGCAUCUUCAAGAAGGUGACUGUGCCUCUCUGAGCCUCAGCCUCCUCUGUCUGACAGCAUAGGGGUCUGCAAGUCUCUAGAGGUCAUGUGAGCUCCAUGGGAACCUCUCAUCUAUACCGUGGAAGCAGCUGCGGGAAGUGCACGUGAGCUCUGUGGCCUCAUGCCGACCAAGACCCUGGGGGUCACACCAGGCAUAGCUGAGAAGCAGAGCAGAGGCCACUGCGGUGACCAGGGUUACUCCCGAGACUCAGAGCAGAGGCCACUGCAGUGACCAGGGUUGCUGCCUGCCUGCCACACACCCCACUUGGGCCUCUGGCUGUCUCCUCUCCUGCAGAAACCCCAUGGGCAGGUGUGCAGCCAGCAUGGAGGGAAGAUGUGUGUGCCAGCAGAGAGAGCACGAGGCCUGGAGUUCUCAUCUGUGCCACCAGAAGCAGGGGACAGUGAAACAUCAUCCAUGACCACUAGGGAGACGGCUCCAUCCCAGGCAUCACAAACCAGCCCAGAAGUGUCACCGGUCUAGUGGCAACAGAAAAAUGCAGACAGAUCAAUAUGGAUGGUCAUGCUCACGUUCCUCAUGGGAAACAGCGCUUCCGAAGAUUCCUCACGGGAAACAGAGCUUCCAAACGUUCCGACUUCCGAUAAGUCCAUGUCUGUUGUGUAUUGGCUGCAAAGAAAACCUCAAGGAACUAAAAAGUAGAAUAAUUAAAAUGAUCCUGUUAUCCAAAAAAUUGUAAAAUAAAUAACGGAAAGUGCCACCUCUUCCCCCAGAAACUUAGAAACCAACACACUCCCAGGUAGCCCUUGGGUAAAACAGGAUAUUAAAUCUGAACGUGCACUCUCUGAAAAGCCGAGAAGCCAUAAAUAUCAAUCCAUAAAUAUCGAGGACUCAGCUAAUGCAGCGCCCAGAGCCCCCAGCACAGCUCUUAUUUUUUAGAGGAAAAAAUAAACGAGAGGGACUUUGUGCCACCCUAAGAAACUAGAAUGAGAACAAUAAAGUGCAUUUUAAAAAGUAGGGAGAAUUAUGAAGAUAAAGCCAGAAAUUAAUGAGUAGAAAACAAAUAAGUAAAAAGGAGAAAUGAUUGUUUUCUGAAAGAAAUAAAAUAAAAUCCCCUUGCCCAGCCCAAAAGCUGCAUCAAGAAAUGACUGCCUAGGCUGGGCGUGGUGGCUCACGCCUGUAAUGCUUACACUUUGGGAGGCUGAGGUGUGCAGAUCACUUGAGGCCUGGAGUUUGAGACCAUCCUGGCCAAUAUAGUGAAACCGUGUCUUUGCAAAAAUACACAAAUUAGCCGGGCAUGGUGGUGCGUGCCCGUAGUCCCAGCUACUUGGGAGGCUAAGACAGAACAAUUGCUUGAAUCCGGGAGGUGGAGGCUGCAGUGAACUGAGAUCGUCCCACUGCACUCCAGCCUGGGUGAUAAAGUGAGACUCUGUUUCAAAAAAAAAAAAAAACUAAAACAAAUAAAUGACUACCUCUAUUUAGAAUUUUUGUACAUUGAAAUAAAAAAACCCACACAUGAUUAGGAAGAAAGAGACCCCAGUAUGGAAGAGGCUGGAGGAAUGAUGAGACAGCCCGCUCGGCCGGGGCAGCUGCUUCGAAACCUGCAGCAGCCAUGUUGUCGUGGGUGUAAAGUCCAGAAUGACUCUGGAUGAGCGGCACCACGCAGAGAUGAGCACGAGGUGCUGGAGAGGGCGAGAGCUGAGCCAGGAAAGGAGGCACCAGGAGCAGAUGUCCGCAGCUGACGAUGACCUCACCUUCCAUGGAAGGAAAGUCAUCCCAGGGUUACUUUAACCUUCCCAAGACAUGAAAGGAUGGAAAACUCUGUAAUUCAUCUCAUGAAACCAGGAUAAUCUAAUUCAAAAACCUGAUGUGGAACAAAAAGAGAAAACCAUAGACAAAUAUCACUUUUCGCAGAUGCAAAAAAAUCUAAGUAAGAGAACAGCAAAUAGGACUCAAUGCAGCAUCAGCGGAUUCUACACAAGAGAACAGCAAAUAGGAACCAACGCAGCGUCGGCGGAUUCUACACAAGAGAACAGCAAAUAGGACCCAACACAGCGUCGGCAGCAUCGUGUUAUGGCCAAGCAGAUGAAGGCCAGGCUUACGAGGGCAGCGCAGUCAUCAGAGACGUCAUUUCAUUAGCCAAUUAGCACAGAAAAUUCAGAGAACCUCACCGACAGGUACUGAAAAGAAAACUGACCAAAUUCAGCAAUCUUUAUGAAUAAAAGCACUAUUUCUAGUAAAAUAGAAAAAAGUGCAAAAGUCUCUGUCCACAAUAGUGGCCAAGAUCGUUCUACGUGGAAAACACAAAUGUCACAAAUCCAGGGUCGACUCGUGGGGCCUGCUGCUGUCAUAAUUGUCCAGCAUUUUCUCGGAGGUUCUGGCAAACUUAAUAGAAAAACCAAAUAAAUGGCACAAAUAUCAGAAAAAUAAGACAAUUUAUUUUGUUGAUGACAUGAUUGUAAACCUAGUUAUGCCUCUGCUCCCUCAUUUAAAAAUUAAAAAUCAGGCCAGGUGCGGUGGCUCACGCCUGUAAUCCCAGCACUUUGGGAGGCCAAGGUGGGCAGAUCACCUGAGAUCAGGAGUUCGAGACCAGCCUGACCAACAUAGUGAAAUCCUGUCUCUACUAAAAACACAAAAUUAGCCGGGCGUGGUGGUGCAUGCCUGUAAUCCCAGCUACUCGGGGGUCUGAGGCACGAGAAUCGCUUGAACCCAUGGGUGGAGGUUGCAGCGAGCCGAAAUCACACCACUGCACUCCAGCCUAGGCCAGAAGAGUGAAACUCCAUCUCAAAAAAUAUUAAAAUUAAAAUUAAAAAUCAGUAAAAACAUUUUAAUACAAGAUAAAUAUACAAAAAUUAGUAACUUCCCACUCCUCUAGCAAUAAUCACCUGGAAAUUUUAAAAAAAGGGAGUCAAAAUAUUCCCUUUGCCAUGGCAACUGAGUAGUUGGGGGUGAAGGUUAGGAUGCUGUAUGGAGCAGCUCCGGCCAUGGGGAGCUCGACAGAGGCGUCAUUUCUCUCCCACAUGGUGGCUGAGAAUAGCUGGGUGUGCUGCUCUGUCGCCACACAUGGGGUCCCCCCAUCACGCCUCUUCUCUAGCCUUCCAGGCAUCUUUCCUGGCUGUGGGGUUCUACUGGGUGCAGAAAUGCCCACGUCCAGCUGGCAGGAGGGGCCGGGGCCAGGGCAGGAGAGGAGAGGCCAUGUUUUCCAAGACCGGAGCUGGCAGGAACAGUGUCUCCAGGUGACAAAAGCCUCCGACAAUUUGGCGAGAAAGGUGGGGGUGGGCAUGAGAGGAUGCAGGGCCCCCACCACUCAAGCAAGGAGAGCGGGGGGCAGAGCCACGGAGAAGACCCAGUCUGGAGCCUCUCCCCCCAGCCUGAAGCCCAGCCUCCAGGUUCCAUGAAAUCACCUCCAGUUAUUCCAGGAGAAACGGCGCACGGCCUAGGAAAGAAAGAACAGGCAGCUUGGACCCAGGCUCCAAUCCCGGCUGCUAGUUACCAGACGGGCAGCCACAUCGCGUCUGUGUGCCUCAGUUUCUACACCUGCGGCUGGGUUGAUGGUUGUGUCCGCCCGGUGGGGCUGCUGUGAGUUAAGGGGUGAGAAACGCUUCCCUGUCCACUGUCUCUGACACGUUCUUCCUGGGUCACCCCUCACUCAACACCCCCAGAGACCAGGCAGGCUCCACGGACAGUUGAGAAGGCGUCCAGCCUGCAGAACGGAGUCCAGGACCCAGAGAAGCUUCAGGGGAUGUUAUGGAUCUGGCAGGGAACGUGUAAACCAUGAGCUCACCCCACGGGAACGUGGUUUCCUCUGGCUGCCCCCACAACAGCUGUUCCCCAUCAGCACCGGCCCCAUCUCCCUAGCAGGAAGCUGGGCAGCCACUGCAGGCCAGGUGUGGACGACCCUCACAACUCUCCCAUCUGCGUGGACAUCGCUGGACGGGGUGAAGACGUCCUGUGCCUGUUAGCAACCGCUCCCCGCCACGGUUUGAGUGAGGCCACAACAGAACAUCAGACAGCAGUUUAUCAACAGAGACUUCCUGCCUCCCCGUCUGGAGGCCAAGGGCCCUUAUAAAAGGGCUAGAAGGAACUAGCUUGGCUGUUUUUCCUCCGAAUUCUGCCAUGUGAGGCUGGAUACGCCAUUGGAGCUGCCCUCAGCAGACCCCAGCCUGCCGGCACCUGGAUCUUGGACUCCCCAGCUUGAGAACUACAGGAAAUAAAUUUCUGUUGCUUAUAAAUUA